GAGCAGAGGGAGAUACAGAAACCGACAGGGGCCAGGCGCCCGGUGGCUCCGAAGCGGGGAAGUGGGACAAGAUGGUUUACAUCUCGAACGGACAAGUGUUGGACAGCCGGAGUCAGUCUCCAUGGAGAUUAUCUUUGAUAACAGAUUUCUUCUGGGGAAUAGCUGAGUUUGUGGUUUUGUUUUUCAAAACUCUGCUUCAGCAAGAUGUGAAAAAAAGAAGAAGCUAUGGAAACUCAUCUGAUUCCAGAUAUGAUGAUGGAAGAGGGCCACCAGGAAACCCUCCCCGAAGAAUGGGUAGAAUCAAUCAUCUGCGUGGCCCUAGUCCCCCUCCAAUGGCUGGUGGAUGAGGAAGGUAAAUGUCUGCUCUAAGAAGCAGACAACCGGACAUGCGCAUUCAUAGCAGAAGGAAACCAUCAAGAAGUGGAAGGCUGACCAUGAUGAGCAGUAGAUGAAUGUGUAUGUCUAAACAAGGACUGCUCUGUGUCCUCACAGAUGAAUGAGGUCAUGCUGGGAAUUCCCUCUGCAGGGAACUGGCCUGACUGACAUGCAGUUCCAUAAAUGCAGAUGUUUGUCUCAUUACCUUUUUGUAUAGUUUAUUAAAGUAUUAAUAUAGUUUUAAUAAGUAAAUAUUUUUAGGUUGCAGAAUGGACUCCUCAUCUUUAUAUUCACGAAAAAGCAAUCUGAAGAAAACAAAUAAAAGCCUGUGUAUUUAGCACUGUUAGUGUCACCUUUUCAACUUCUGAAACACUGUUCAUUGUUAACUUUUUCUCAUUUAUAAAUCACUGUAUUUAUUUUAGUAGUAUGCAUAGCAUAUCUGUGCUCUUGAAUUAAUUUUUAUCUUUAACAUAUUUGUCUCAUCAAUCUUUAAUACACUGUGUCUAAUUUGCUACCAAAUGUAAUUAUCAGGGUAUUUAUAAAACCAUAGCUAACAAAACUGAGCUACAAAAUGAAAAUUUACUAAAUAGUUUUUAAAAUCAUGGACUUCAGCCUGGCGCGGUGGCUCAUGCCUGUAAUCCCAGCACUGUGGGAGGCUGAGGCGGGCAGAUCGCCUAAGUUCACGAGUUUGAGACCAGCCUGCAGCAUGACGAAACCUAAAAUAACAAAAAUUAGCCAGGCGUGGUAGAGUGCACCUGUAAUCCCUGCUACUCAGGAGGCGGAGGCAGGAGAAUCGCUUCAACCCGGGAGGCGGAGGUUGCUGUGAGCAUGCCACUGCACUCCUGCCUAGGCAACAGAGUGAGACCCUGUCUCAAAAAAAUAAAUAAAACCAUGGGCUUCCAUGCUAUCUUGACAAAUUUGCACUCUAUAGCAUCACUCAAAAUACUGCCUAUUGGCUUUAAACUCCAUCUGAAUACUGAUAACUUUCACAUUCUUUCACUAGAGUGGAAGCUCUGAGACUAGGAAUUUUGUUGUCUUUACCCCAGUCCUUUGAAUAGUGACUACAUGUAAGAUAGUCAUGUAGUAUUUAUUGGAAAUAAAUAUUUAUUGGAAAAACGAAAA